CCCGAACAUCACGGUCAGUGGGCCAGAAGGACAGGGAAAGGAGCUACUCCUUCUCUUAUACUUGGGGUGACCUCGGGCAACUCACCAGCGCCCCUCCCCAAGCCUCAGUUUAUCUGGCUGUGAAGUGGGGAGUCCAGCGAACCCAGCUGUGAGGCUCAAUAUGCUAACUAUGGCACAGAACUGCCGAGACGAGCUGGUUAACUUGUUCACACUACAUCGUGUUGGACUGACAAGGCUCCCAGGGCUCAGCACCUUUGAAGGUGUGCACGUCAUCACCCUAAAGUCAAACCACGGGCGCCAGCUGGAGGGGGUGCAGACCACAGAUGGGAAGACUGGACUGCUCGAAGUUACAGCACUGCCGUUCGAAGCCACGCAAGAAAUCGGGGCAGGGACGGGGGCAGCAUGGGUGCCAGGUGGAGGUGCAGAGAGAGCGCUGGGUGGUUCCUGGGCCCUGGGUUCUAGUCCCAGUCCAGCUAGCCACUGACUGUAUAACCUGGGACGACUCCCCUGCCUCCAUUUCCUCAUCUGCACAGUGAGGGUUUGGGCAGAAUUCCCCCAGCUUUGACUCACGGCAGGGCCCUACUUGGGGGGCGCUAUGCUGCCCAAUGGACGCUCCCUGCCACCCCUGGCUUCAGGAGGCAACGGGAGGAAGAGCAGGACCGGAAAACACAGCCCCAAACAGUCUGUCUCCUCCUCCCCCACCUCCCACUGCCCCACGGCCCUCAACUCUGAUCUCACCUCUCUGGAGGCUGAGGGUGACGAGAACAGUCUGUUUGGUAGGUCACGGGGAGGGGCGGGCAGAGUUGUGCUCACCAGCUGCAGCCAGGCCUCAGAGCAGCAUCCGUGGGUCCCACCCCCGCACAUAUCUCUCCCGCCUCCAGGACCCUGGAGACCCUCCAGGCCUGGCUGACUGGGUACAUCCUCAGCUCUCUGGCUCCUGCUCGUGGAAGCCCUGCUCUUUCAGCCUGGCCUGGCCCUUUCAAACCGGAAGGAUCUCUUCCCACAGAGACCACUGGGGCCAAACCAUCAUUUGCGCAGGGAAAGACAUUGACCUUUUCAGUCCCAGCAAAUGAGAAGCAUGGCCUAGGGUUCUGACCCCAGGAUCGCCCACCUACCCAGGUCCCCAAGCCAGAAGGUGGCUCCUGCAGAGCCCCUCUUCUUAAGGCCCCACCAUGCACAUAGAUGACCCCAUGGCAAUGCCAACUUUGGUCUGGUUGAUUCUAGGGCUCUUCUGAGGAAUGAAGCCCAUCUCCAACCUGCUUCCCCCUCCCUUCCCCACCGUAUGUACCCACACCCAUGACCCAGCUACCGAGUCUGCCUGCUUCUGGUCAGUCAGGGGGUCUUGGCCUCUGCUUGGUUCUGACUCCUCAGGCUCCUCUGGUUGGAACUGGAGAUUAAAAAAAGAACACAGCUUAGCCCAA